GGGGCGCAGCCGCCUGUCUGCACCGGCAGCACCAUGUUGCUCAUGGUCGUCAGCAUGGCGUGUGUUGGGUUCUUCUUGGUCCAGAGGGCCGGUCCACACAUGGGUGGUCAGGACAAGCCCUUCCUGUCUGCCUGGCCCAGCGCUGUGGUGCCUCGAGGAGGACACGUGACUCUUCGGUGUCACUAUCGUCAUAGGUUUAACAAUUUCAUGCUAUACAAAGAAGACAGAAUCCACGUUCCCAUCUUCCAUGGCAGAAUAUUCCAGGAGGGCUUCAACAUGAGCCCUGUGACCACAGCACAUGCAGGGAACUACACAUGUCGGGGUUCACACCCACACUCCCCCACUGGGUGGUCGGCACCCAGCAACCCCAUGGUGAUCAUGGUCACAGGAAACCACAGAAAACCUUCCCUCCUGGCCCACCCAGGUCCCCUGGUGAAAUCAGGAGAGAGAGUCAUCCUGCAAUGUUGGUCAGAUAUCAUGUUUGAGCACUUCUUUCUGCACAAAGAGGGGAUCUCUAAGGACCCCUCACGCCUCGUUGGACAGAUCCAUGAUGGGGUCUCCAAGGCCAAUUUCUCCAUCGGUUCCAUGAUGCGUGCCCUUGCAGGGACCUACAGAUGCUACGGUUCUGUUACUCACACCCCCUAUCAGUUGUCAGCUCCCAGUGAUCCCCUGGACAUCGUGGUCACAGGU